ACACAAUGCCUCGGGACUGUCCCGGGAGGUGAGGCCCCCACGAUUGGCGAGAAAGCUAUUUUGCAUAUGAUUUGCAUCUUACGAAGAAUUUGUGGCAAAAAAAAGCUGGGCGUGCGCCGUAGGAACCUCCUGCUGAGACGCUUCCGGUAGCGGCGCGUGACCCGACAGGUCUUUCACCUACCUACCUCAGCUCCCACAAACACGAGAAGUUCCAGCAAGUUCGCCACUUCCGGUUCUCCUGGCUAUCCAAUAGCAUCGAGAGGAGCAUCCCCGGAAGUGAGGCAGCGGAGGACGACCUUUUUCCGGUUCCGGCCUGGCGAGAGUUUGUGCGGCGACAUGAAACUGCUUACCCACAAUCUGCUGAGCUCGCAUGUGCGGGGGGUGGGGUCCCGUGGCUUCCCCCUGCGCCUCCAGGCCACCGAGGUCCGUAUCUGCCCUGUGGAAUUCAACCCCAACUUCGUGGCGCGUAUGAUACCUAAAGUGGAGUGGUCGGCGUUCCUGGAGGCGGCCGAUAACUUGCGUCUGAUCCAGGUGCCGAAAGGGCCGGUUGAGGGAUAUGAGGAGAAUGAGGAGUUUCUGAGGACCAUGCACCACCUGCUGCUGGAGGUGGAAGUGAUAGAGGGCACCCUGCAGUGCCCGGAAUCUGGACGUAUGUUCCCCAUCAGCCGCGGGAUCCCCAACAUGCUGCUGAGUGAAGAGGAAACUGAGAGUUGAUUGUGCCAGGCGCCAGUUUUUCUUGUUAUGACUGUGUAUUUUUGUUGAUCUAUACCCUGUUUCCGAAUUCUGCCGUGUGUAUCCCCAACCCUUGACCCAAUGACACCAAACACAGUGUUUUUGAGCUCGGUAUUAUAUAUUUUUUUCUCAUUAAAGGUUUAAAACCAAAAGCGGUUUCUCUUUGCAGCAAAUAUACAUUAAAAUAGAGUCUCUGUACAGCCAAGGGCUCUGGGCCCUGGCUUGCCCCAUGUCCCUGCGCCUCCCUGGCCAAACCCAAAAAUAAAUAUAGUGUUAUUGCUCUGCAGGGCAUAGAGGCAGUGCUCUCCUACCCCCUGAGGAGGCUCGUUGGGAGCUGAUGGGGAAGCCCUGGCCACCCCAGGGGUCCAGGGGCUGGAGUCUGC